AAUCAGGCGCGUCCCUCUGGCGCUGGAGCCAGGACCUGGCGUUGGGCGGUACUUGGACAGCGGUUCUUGAGCUCUCGCGGUUGCCGGUAGAUUGUUGCCAGUUGCCAGUUGCCAGUCGUUUUUCGGAAAGCUGGCAGCGGCUUUUUCACCGGGUUCUGCUUGAGGCCGAGCCAAAGAGUGGCUGUGACUCGGGAGACGGAGUGGAACACCCGGCUGGGCAGGCCCGGACAGCUCCCGCGACCCAGCACCGCAGGAUCAGACCGUGCCUCUGCGGGGAGAGGCUGGAGAGGAAGAGUCCGGCCUGGGAGCCGUCAGAGCAGCCCUGCAGAACGGGGUGGGGGCUGCUGUAGAUAGACCCUUACGCCCAGAGAACUGCUGGGAGGCUGUGGCGCGAGGCGGGACUCAAAUGCUGGAGGAAGGAGGUGAGGAGUGGUAGAGGGAGCGAUUGUCAAGAGAUCGGCUGCUGCUUCGUUUGCCCACGACUGCCGCUGUGUGAGCCGAAUCAGAACUCUCUUUAUCUCUCCUACAGAUGAGAAAAAUGAGACUUAGAGAGGUUACGUGAUUUGCACACUGCUGCUGAGUGGUGGAUCAUGGAUACUUGAGAGUCUGUGAACACUCUAAUGCCUCCCUACAUCUGAGUGAGUUGAUGGAAUUUCUGAGUACUGCCUUCCCCAGGCCCUGCCCUUCCCCAAGAGGAAAACACAGGAGAGGAAGGAAUGGCUGCUGGUCUCCUCACAGCUGGGCCCCGGGGAUCCACAUUCUUCAGCAGUGUGACGGUAGCUUUUGCACAGGAAAGGUGGAGGUGCCUCGUGUCUACUCCACGGGACAGGUUCAAGGAGGGGAUACCAGGAAAGUCCAGGAGCCUUGUCCUACUAGGACUUCCAGUUUCCCAGCCUGGCAUGAACUCCCAGUUGGAACAAAGGGAAGGCGCAUGGAUGCUGGAGGGCGAAGACCUGCGAAGUCCCUCUCCAGGCUGGAAGAUUAUAUCUGGAUCACCACCAGAGCAAGCCCUUUCUGAAGCUUCAUUCCAAGACCCAUGUGUAGAGAUGCCCCCUGGGGAUUCAGACCACGGGACCAGUGACCUUGAGAAGAGCUUCAAUCUGAGACCAGUCCUCUCUCCGCAACAGAGAGUGCCCGUGGAAGCGAGACCUCGCAAAUGUGAGACACACACCGAGAGCUUCAAGAACUCGGAAAUCCUGAAACCUCACAGAGCAAAACCAUAUGCAUGUAAUGAAUGUGGCAAAGCCUUCAGUUACUGUUCUUCCCUUUCUCAGCAUCAGAAGAGCCACACUGGAGAGAAGCCCUAUGAGUGCAGUGAAUGUGGGAAGGCCUUCAGCCAGAGCUCAUCUCUCAUUCAGCACCAGAGGAUUCACACUGGAGAGAAGCCUUACAAGUGCAGUGAAUGUGGAAGAGCCUUCAGCCAGAACGCCAACCUCACCAAACACCAGCGAACCCACACCGGAGAGAAGCCCUACAGAUGCAGCGAGUGUGAGAAAGCCUUCAGUGACUGCUCAGCUCUUGUUCAGCAUCAGAGAAUUCAUACCGGAGAGAAGCCCUACGAAUGCAGCGACUGUGGGAAGGCCUUCCGUCACAGUGCAAACCUCACGAACCAUCAGAGGACUCACACCGGGGAGAAGCCCUACAAGUGCAGCGAGUGUGGGAAGGCCUUCAGUUACUGCGCAGCGUUCAUUCAGCACCAGAGGAUUCACACCGGGGAGAAGCCCUACAGAUGUGCCGCGUGUGGGAAGGCCUUCAGCCAGAGUGCAAACCUCACAAACCAUCAGAGGACUCACACUGGGGAGAAACCCUACAAGUGCAGCGAGUGUGGGAAGGCCUUCAGCCAGAGUACCAAUCUCAUAAUCCACCAAAAGACCCACACCGGGGAGAAGCCAUAUAAAUGUAAUGAAUGUGGGAAAUUCUUCAGUGAGAGCUCAGCCCUCAUUCGGCAUCAUAUAAUCCACACCGGAGAAAAACCUUAUGAGUGUAAUGAGUGUGGUAAAGCGUUUAACCAGAGCUCAUCCCUUAGUCAGCAUCAGAGAAUCCACACAGGCGUGAAACCCUACGAAUGCAGCGAGUGUGGGAAGGCCUUCCGGUGCAGCUCUGCCUUCGUUAGACAUCAGAGACUCCACGCCGGAGAGUAACUAGGAACAUGGUAGAAGUGGAGAGAGUCCCGGACAUGCCGACUCAGGACAGGUGGGUGAGGAUCUGAGAAAUGCUAAAGGCUUGAAAGCAUCUGAAGACAUCUAACUUAGAGUCUGCAGCCCAGAGCCACAUGCAAAACACCUUCAAUAAACAGCCACUAUUUCACAUGCUGUA